GCUGUCCUCACCGCAAUGGCGGCUGUGAGGGCCCUGGUGGCCUCGAGGCUCGCUGCGGCAUCUGCAUUCACGUCCCUGUCCCCCGGCGGUCGGACGCCUUCCCAGCGCGCAGCCCUUCACCUCUCCGUGCCGCGCCCCGCGGCCAGGGUCGCGCUGGUGCUGUCUGGAUGCGGAGUCUACGAUGGGACCGAGAUCCACGAGGCCUCGGCGAUCCUGGUGCACCUGAGCCGUGGAGGGGCUGAAGUCCAGAUCUUUGCUCCUGACGUCCCUCAGAUGCACGUGAUUGACCACACCAAGGGGCAGCCGUCCGAAGGCGAGAGCAGGAAUGUUUUGACCGAGUCUGCGAGGAUCGCCCGUGGCAAAAUCACAGACCUGGCCAACCUCAGUGCAGCCAACCAUGAUGCUGCCAUCUUUCCAGGAGGCUUUGGAGCGGCUAAAAACCUGAGCACGUUUGCCGUGGACGGGAAAGAUUGCAAGGUGAAUAAAGAAGUGGAGCGUGUCCUGAAGGAGUUCCACCAGGCCGGGAAGCCCAUCGGCUUGUGCUGCAUUGCACCUGUCCUCGCGGCCAAGGUGCUCAGAGGCGUCGAGGUGACUGUGGGCCACGAGCAGGAGGAAGGUGGCAAGUGGCCUUAUGCCGGGACCGCAGAGGCCAUCAAGGCCCUGGGUGCCAAGCACUGCGUGAAGGAAGUGGUCGAAGCUCACGUGGACCAGAAAAACAAGGUGGUCACGACCCCAGCCUUCAUGUGCGAGACGGCACUCCACUACAUCCAUGAUGGGAUCGGAGCCAUGGUGAGGAAGGUGCUGGAACUCACUGGAAAGUGACGCGCAUGGACGGGGCCCAGCUAGGCGCCAGGACUUGGCCUCACCCUCUGGCUGAGGAGCUGUCGGCUGCUUUCCAUCCAGCUGGGAGUCUGGCAGGCCCUUUUUUUUUUUUCUUUGCCGAAACCUGCAGGCGUUCUCUCUCUAAGGAGGAUGUGCUGCAGUGCAUGGGGGAUGUUUCUUCCUGGGUGUGGCUGGGCUGCUCUCACAUACAGAGGCCGAGGGGCCAAUUCGUUCUCUGCCACAGGGACUUGCCUCACUGUGUCCCAAAAACAAAUCGCAGCCAGCUUUUCCAGAAAUAGAAAAUUCUGCCGUCUGAGGUUUUAUACUUCAGGUUAGUUAGUUUUUGGAAGGAAGAACAUUUUUAGGUUUGCAAGCCUCCUGAUCAGGAAACCAGAAAUACCACAUUUAUGGACCAUGAAAGGUUGGUUCUUGACUCUGAAGGGACUUUUGAGUUAAUCAGCGUAAGGGGAUUUCUAAAGCAGGCAAUCCCUGUAGCCGCAGAGAAUAAACGCCUUCCCAAAAUGGCAACUUCCCACAGCCACAUUUCAGACCUGCUGAGACUGCUGAGUGAGGAAUGGCAGUGAGGUUUCUUCAAUUAGUCUCAGUUCUCUUAAUUUUCAGGAAGAAAGGGAAAUUGCAGCUCCUCAGCCCCCAGGAUUGACCUCUGGGGAGUGAUGGUAGCGUUGGUGCCAGGCCGUGGGUUCAGGUGUGGCAGAAGCUUGCAGAUGCGUCCGAAGGGAAAUAAAGUGUGUUGGCGUUAGA